GUUAGAGGGGGUGGUCAAGACCCCAGGAUUCCGUGGGAGACCACUGGAGAGAGGGCACUCGGCGCAGAGGAAGGCAACCUGAGGUGUGCUUUUUGACAGGUGCCUUGGAAGCUGCUGAGAACAGCACAGGGGCAGCCAGGGGGCCCUGGAACCCGAGGGUGGGGAGGAAGUGAAGAAGCGGGGGAGGGCAGAUGAGGGAGACUGGUUAUCCAGGAAUCUGGCAGCAACUUGGAAGCUGUUAGGAUGGAGAUGGAGGUGAGAGGCCUCCCGGAAAGCCUUGCCCCUCGCCUCUUUCUCCUCUCUUUCUUCCCUGAUCGGGGAAGGGGGCGGCGAGGCUCCUCAGCCCUGCACCAGCGGGACCUGACCUUGGUGGGUACCAGGCCGCUGUAGGUUGAGAUAAUGUGCAGAGGCAGAUGGAGCCUGAGAUAGCUCGGUGUGGCUCUUACCUCUCCAGACUUUCUCCUGGUUGUUUGGCAUUUCUUUGCUCACAUGCUGCACACACACACAUACAUUCACCCUCUCCAUGUAUGUCCUAGAGUCCCCGGACCACGAUGUUGUUGACACGGUCUGUGGGCAGAGUGUCUUGGGGAAUGCGGACUUUAAACCUUGUCUGUGACCUUGGGGGUCAGGUCCCUGUAAAGCAACCAAGGUGAAUUUCUUGGACUCUUCAUCUUGUGUGGUGGGGGUGGAGGUGUCCCAGAAGUGUAUGUAGCAAGAUGUGGGUCAAAAAAAGAAUAUAAGCGGAAAGAAAAUGAGAGUUGAGAUUCUCGGUAGUUUCUGGGAGCACUUACUUUCAUUCAUUCAUUCAUUCGUUCAUUCAGCGCUUCCUGGAUGCCUCCUCUACACUCAGCACCAUGCUGAAUGUCUCAUGAAUGUAAUCUGGAAGGUAAAUAUUUAGUGCUAGAGAGCAUCUCUUAGGCAAGCUGCUUCAACCUCUGAGCCUCAGUUUCCCUGUUUGUCAGAUGGGGGAGCCCACCAUUUCCCUGAAUUUAAAAAGUUUGCUUGGAAGGGAAUAUUGGGAUGCUUAAAACUUGGAAGGGACGUACAUCAGCGCCCAACUCCCAUUUGAAACAUAAGAGAAAAUUUGAAGCCCAGAGGUGUGAUUUGCUCAAGUAUUUUGAUUUUUCUGCCAUUCUGCGUACCAGUUCUUCACCAGCUCUGAAGUUCUAACCUGCAAACUUGUCACCCUGACACACUGCUUCCCCACCCUUACUCGGGUCAGUUGCCAGCUCUGCUACUGUGUUGGUGAACUUGGCAGCACCUUUUCUCUUGUCCUUUUCUCAGAACAGACACAAGUUCAAACAUAUGUGACCUGCCCCAAUUUAGGUCCCUGUAGUUUACGGAGGCCUGUGUGCUGUUAGCAGGUGGACGUCCUGUUGGAGGGAAAGGACCGCCCCUGCCAACACUGAUAAUCAUGCAUCUGGGGACUUCUAAUACAGCAAUAGGAGGCCCCUCUCAACAGUAAUUCUUUACCCUUGGAAAAGGGUAAGUAAGUAGCUUCUAUGAAGAACUGAUUGGCUGGAGCACAAUCUCCCAAAUUUUAGUGUUACAUGGACCACCUCCAUGAUUUUUUUUUGCUAUAUCCACCUGUGCUAUUGCUUACUUACUCCUUGACUUUAGAUCAACUCACUUUAAAAAUAUGUGUACCAUUUUCACAAAUGGGAAACUAGUUAUAUCUAUUGUCAUACAGGGGAAACAAAAAAGAUAGGCAAACAAAAAAAACAAAAAACCAGGGUUAGUAUAUUUUAGCUAGGUACUGUGGCCAGCCUAAGGCCACAGCACCUCACCUGCCCAGCCUUUGUUUUUAAGCAGAUUGGCAAGCCAUGGAGAGGCGGCAGAAACAUAGUGGCACUUAGGUGAGCAGCUCACCUUCUUCAUCUUGUGUCAUUGGUUUUUUUGUUUGCUUUUGGUUUUUUUGUUUAUUUGUUUUUGUUUUUUGGAGACAGAGUCUCGCUCUGUCGCCCAGGCUGGAGUCCAGUGGUGCGAUCUUGGCUCACUGCAAGUCUGCCUCCUGGGUUCAAGCGAUUCUCCUGCCUCAACCUCCCGAGUAGCUGGGACUACAGGUGCACGCCACCACAUCCAGCCAAUUUUUUGUAUUUUAGUAGAGAUGGGGUUUCACUGUGUUGCCCAGGCUAGUCUUGAACUCCUGAGCUCAGGCAAUCCGCCCACCUCAGCCUCCCAAAGUGCUAGGAUUACAGGCGUGAGCCACCACGCUUGGCCUUGGGUCACUGGUUUAUAAACUUCAUCUCUGUACCUCCUUGUCAUCCCACCUGGACUGGGGUGGUAUUGGGCCCCUGAACUUGGGGUCCUGAGGGGGUCUCAUGUCAACUCUGGGGGUCACUAUUGUGGUCCAGCUUUGUAUGUUUUGGAAAAGUGCUAAUUGGAGGAUAGCCACUUGUGGUUUUCUGGAAUUUCCCUCCGGCAUACCCCAUUUUUGCCUUUUAGUUCUGUCUGUGUGGCCUUGGGCAAAUCACUUGACCUCUCUGAGGUUUGAGUGCUUGAGAAGUGGGUUGGUUAGAUGGUCUUCAAGGGCCUGCCAGCUCUUAAAUAUUAUUUCAAACCCUUCUGCCGCUCUUACCUCUCCAGACUCCAUGAGAGGAGAAGGGGGAACAGGGAUGGGCUAUGAGAAAAAGGAAGAAGAAAUUUAACAAAGCUGAAAAGAGCCAAACUUAUUCCGGGGGGUGGUGGGUUGGGGAGAAAAAAUUCUGCCAAGGUAGUUAUAUCCCUGCAAUUAAUUAAUGCUGUGAGACAAAAAAUUGCACUAAAAAUUUCUACUCCGUGUGUGUGUGUGUGUGUGUGUGUGUGUGUGUGUGUUUAUUUGCCUUGGAUUUUUCCUUACCUGAAUCAUGGAGAUGCCCACCCAUUCCCCUGAAUUUAAAAGAAGUAAGUCAAAUGGUCCUUCAGUCAGAAAAGUGAUUUCUUAGCCACCAAGGACAAAAUAGCGUCUCUGGUUACCAACCCUAAAGAAUGUCUUGGCACAUUCCUCCCUCUGGGGCUGAGCUGUUUUGUGUGCUGGCCGGCCAGGAGCUGCUGGGGGUAGGGAAUCCAGUUUUCAGCUUCCCCUUUCACCAGGGGGUUGGAAGAGCAGCCAAGCAGCCAGCCUUGCCAACUCUCUCCCCUUCUCACCCAGGGGAAGACUGGGAGGCCGAAAUUCCUGAGGAUGGUUGUCCCAACAACCGGAGAGGGUCCAGUGGGCAGCUUGGGUCCUGCCCACUGGGCCAAAGGCUCCAGCAGCACCACAGGCUUUUCCUGAGUCAAGGCCAGCCUGGGAAGGUGACAGGCCCUUCGGGAAUCAGGUGCUGUGGAUCAGGUCUGAACAGCACCUUGGAGCCGUGCUCCUUUUGCGGAGUAACUCUGGGUGCUUUUGUGAGCUCUAGCGAAGGGGCCAGCGUCCUGUGUAUUUCACUUCGUGGUAUGCAAAACAAAUGCACCGAUUGUUCUCGGAGGAAGAAUAGAUCUUUGGGGCUGGCCCUCCCAGAGAAGGUUCCUGCAGCCUGAUUCCUUCUUGUUGUGCGAUUUGUAUUCAGACCUUCUCAUAGGAACCACCUGGGAAUUCUGGGCAGUUUCUGGGUCUGUAUGGUACACCAAACCGCUCACCUUUGCUGACUGCAUUAGUGAUGAGUUGCCGCUAGGAUGGGAAGAGGCAUAUGACCCACAGGUUGGAGAUUACUUCAUAGACCACAACACCAAAACCACUCAGAUUGAGGAUCCUCGAGUACAAUGGCGGCGGGAGCAGGAACAUAUGCUGAAGGAUUACCUGGUGGUGGCCCAGGAGGCUCUGAGUGCACAAAAGGAGAUCUACCAGGUGAAGCAGCAGCGCCUGGAGCUUGCACAGCAGGAGUACCAGCAACUGCAUGCCGUCUGGGAGCAUAAGCUGGGCUCCCAGGUCAGCUUGGUCUCUGGUUCAUCAUCCAGCUCCAAGUAUGACCCUGAGAUCCUGAAAGCUGAAAUUGCCACUGCAAAAUCCCGGGUCAACAAGCUGAAGAGAGAGAUGGUUCACCUCCAGCACGAGCUGCAGUUCAAAGAGCGUGGCUUUCAGACCCUGAAGAAAAUCGAUAAGAAAAUGUCUGAUGCUCAGGGCAGCUACAAACUGGAUGAAGCUCAGGCUGUCUUGAGAGAAACAAAAGCCAUCAAAAAGGCUAUUACCUGUGGGGAAAAGGAAAAGCAAGAUCUCAUUAAGAGCCUUGCCAUGUUGAAGGACGGCUUCCGCACUGACAGGGGGUCUCACUCAGACCUGUGGUCCAGCAGCAGCUCUCUGGAGAGUUCGAGUUUCCCGCUACCGAAACAGUACCUGGAUGUGAGCUCCCAGACAGACAUCUCGGGAAGCUUCGGCAUCAACAGCAACAAUCAGUUGGCAGAGAAGGUCAGAUUGCGCCUUCGAUAUGAAGAGGCUAAGAGAAGACUUUCCUGUCAAUGUGGCCAGGCAACUCCCAGCAAUUCGGAGCUUACACACUACCAGCUCCCCCAGGCGUCCAGCAAAACAGCAAGACAUCUGUAUUUGGACAGCCACUUCUUGUUCUCUCUGAAGAGGACCACUCUGAACCUUGGAUCUGUUCCAUCCUGCAGGAAUGCCUGUCUUAGAUGGAUCGCCAACCUGAAGAUCCAGCUGGCCAAGCUUGACAGUGAGGCCUGGCCUGGGGUGCUGGACUCAGAGAGGGACCGGCUGAUCCUUAUCAACGAGAAGGAGGAGCUGCUGAAGGAGAUGCGCUUCAUCAGCCCCCGCAAGUGGACCCAGGGGGAGGUGGAGCAGCUGGAGAUGGCCCGGAAGCGGCUGGAAAAGGACCUGCAGGCAGCCCGGGACACCCAGAGCAAGGCGCUGACGGAGAGGUUAAAGUUAAACAGUAAGAGGAACCAGCUUGUGAGAGAACUGGAGGAAGCCACCCGGCAGGUGGCAACUCUGCACUCCCAGCUGAAAAGUCUCUCAAGCAGCAUGCAGUCCCUGUCCUCAGGCAGCAGCCCCGGAUCCCUCACGUCCAGCCGGGGCUCCCUGGUUGCAUCCAGCCUGGACUCCUCCACUUCAGCCAGCUUCACUGACCUCUACUAUGACCCCUUUGAGCAGCUGGACUCAGAGCUGCAGAGCAAGGUGGAGUUCCUGCUCCUGGAGGGGGCCACCGGCUUCCGGCCCUCAGGCUGCAUCACCACCAUCCACGAGGAUGAGGUGGCCAAGACCCAGAAGGCAGAGGGAGGUGGCCGCCUGCAGGCUCUGCGUUCCCUGUCUGGCACCCCAAAGUCCAUGACCUCCCUAUCCCCACGUUCCUCUCUCUCCUCCCCCUCCCCACCCUGUUCCCCUCUCAUGGCUGACCCCCUCCUGGCUGGUGAUGCCUUCCUCAACUCCUUGGAGUUUGAAGACCCGGAGCUGAGUGCCACUCUUUGUGAACUGAGCCUUGGUAACAGCGCCCAGGAAAGAUACCGGCUGGAGGAACCAGGAACGGAGGGCAAGCAGCUGGGCCAAGCUGUGAAUACGGCCCAGGGGUGUGGCCUGAAAGUGGCCUGUGUCUCAGCCGCCGUAUCGGACGAGUCAGUGGCUGGAGACAGUGGUGUGUACGAGGCUUCCGUGCAGAGACUGGGUGCUUCAGAAGCUGCUGCAUUUGACAGUGACGAAUCGGAAGCAGUGGGUGCGACCCGAAUUCAGAUUGCCCUGAAGUAUGAUGAGAAGAAUAAGCAAUUUGCAAUAUUAAUCAUCCAGCUGAGUAACCUUUCUGCUCUGUUGCAGCAACAAGACCAGAAAGUGAAUAUCCGCGUGGCUGUCCUUCCUUGCUCUGAAAGCACAACCUGCCUGUUCCGGACCCGGCCUCUGGACGCCUCAGACACUCUAGUGUUCAAUGAGGUGUUCUGGGUAUCCAUGUCCUAUCCAGCCCUUCACCAGAAGACCUUAAGAGUCGAUGUCUGUACCACCGACAGGAGCCAUCUGGAAGAGUGCCUGGGAGGCGCCCAGAUCAGCCUGGCGGAGGUCUGCCGGUCUGGGGAGAGGUCGACUCGCUGGUACAACCUUCUCAGCUACAAAUACUUGAAGAAACAGAGCAGGGAGCUCAAGCCAGUGGGAGUCAUGGCCCCUGCCUCAGGGCCUGCCAGCACGGUGAGCUGGGACCAGGACGCUGUGUCUGCUCUGUUGGAACAGACAGCAGUGGAGCUGGAGAAGAGGCAGGAGGGCAGGAGCAGCACACAGACACUGGAAGACAGCUGGAGGUAUGAGGAGACCAGUGAGAAUGAGGCAGUAGCCGAGGAAGAGGAGGAGGAGGUGGAGGAGGAGGAGGGAGAAGAGGAUGUUUUCACCGAGAAAGCCUCACCUGAUAUGGAUGGGUACCCAGCAUUAAAGGUGGACAAAGAGACCAACACGGAGACCCCGGCCCCAUCCCCCACAGUGGUGCGACCUAAGGACCGGAGAGUGGGCACCCCGUCCCAGGGGCCAUUUCUUCGAGGGAGCACCAUCAUCCGCUCUAAGACCUUCUCCCCAGGACCCCAGAGCCAGUACGUGUGCCGGCUGAAUCGGAGUGAUAGUGACAGCUCCACUCUGUCCAAAAAGCCACCUUUUGUUCGAAACUCCCUGGAGCGACGCAGCGUCCGGAUGAAGCGGCCGUCCCCACCCCCACAGCCUUCCUCGGUCAAGUCGCUGCGCUCCGAGCGUCUGAUCCGUACCUCGCUGGACCUGGAGUUAGACCUGCAGGCGACAAGAACCUGGCACAGCCAAUUGACCCAGGAGAUCUCGGUGCUGAAGGAGCUCAAGGAGCAGCUGGAACAAGCCAAGAGCCACGGGGAGAAGGAGCUGCCACAGUGGUUGCGUGAGGACGAGCGUUUCCGCCUGCUGCUGAGGAUGCUGGAGAAGCGGCAGAUGGACCGAGCGGAGCACAAGGGUGAGCUUCAGACAGACAAGAUGAUGAGGGCAGCUGCCAAGGAUGUGCACAGGCUCCGAGGCCAGAGCUGUAAGGAACCCCCAGAAGUUCAGUCUUUCAGGGAGAAGAUGGCAUUUUUCACCCGGCCUCGGAUGAAUAUCCCAGCUCUCUCUGCAGAUGACGUCUAAUCGCCAGAAAAGUAUUUCCUUUGUUCCACUGACCAGGCUGUGAACAUUGACUGUGGCUAAAGUUAUUUAUGUGGUGUUAUAUGAAGGUACUGAGUCACAAGUCCUCUAGUGCUCUUGUUGGUUUGAAGAUGAACCGACUUUUUAGUUUGGGUCCUACUGUUGUUAUUAAAAACAGAACAAAAACAAAACACACACACACACAAAAACAGAAACAAAAAAAACCAGCAUUAAAAUAAUAAGAUUGUAUAGUUUGUAUAUUUAGGAGUGUAUUUUUGGGAAAGAAAAUUUAAAUGAACUAAAGCAGUAUUGAGUUGCUGCUCUUCUUAAAAUCGUUUAGAUUUUUUUUGGUUUGUACAGCUCCACCUUUUAGAGGUCUUACUGCAAUAAGAAGUAAUGCCUGGGGGACGGUAAUCCUAAUAGGACGUCCCGCACUUGUCACAGUACAGCUAAUUUUUCCUAGUUAACAUAUUUUGUACAAUAUUAAAAAAAUGCACAGAAACCAUUGGGGGGGAUUCAGAGGUGCAUCCACGGAUCUUCUUGAGCUGUGACGUGUUUUUAUGUGGCUGCCCAACGUGGAGCGGGCAGUGUGAUAGGCUGGGUGGGCUAAGCAGCCUAGUCUAUGUGGGUGACAGGCCACGCUGGUCUCAGAUGCCCAGUGAAGCCACUAACAUGAGUGAGGGGAGGGCUGUGGGGAACUCCAUUCAGUUUUAUCUCCAUCAAUAAAGUGGCCUUUCAAAAAGAAUCUUCCUCUUGCUCUCUUUUUCUUUCCUACCCCUCACUUCAUCUGUUUCCCUGAUUUUUGACUCUCCCCUUUCCAGUCAUUUCUUUCCCACCCAUCCGCAGUCCUGGAAACAUUUAUUUUUUCUUUUGCCCACUGUUUUCAUUUGCUCAUUAAAUUAAAAUGACUGCUCGGCUCAUUGGGAAUCCACAUCCCCAAGUUAGACUGGGGAUAUGCUCUCUGUACUGUCUCCUUCUAUGGAAUUCCACCCCACCCAGAGAGAGAUGACUUCACAGUUUGUUCAUAUGAGCAUCAUCCCAUGUCGUCCCCAACCCAGGGGCUGGUAGGUGCUACAGCUUGUGCUUCAUGCUGCUCCUGUGGCCCCUAUUCCUACCCAGCUCAGAGCUUUGCAGGGUCUACUGCAGACAAUCAGAAGUCAGUUUCUAACAAAUAGCAACAGCCACAAAUCUCUUCCUCCUUCCUCUCUGACAUUACCCUGUGCAACUUUUCUCAAAGUCUGUUGCACCACUCAGCAAAGCAAGUUGCACCAGCUAUAUCAGAAUCACCUGGGGCAGCCUAUUAAAAAUGCAGACUGUUGAGACCAUCCUGGCUAACACGGUGAAACCCUGUCUCUACUAAAAAUACAAAAAAUUAGCCGGCCGUGGUGGCGGGCAGCUACUCGGGAGGCUGAGGCAGGAGAAUGACCUGAACCUGGGAGGCAGAGCUUGCAGUGAGCUGAGAUUGUGCCACUGCACUCCAGCCUGGGUGACAGAGCAAGACUCCGUCUCAAAAAAAAAAAAAAAAGAAAAAUGCAGACUGGCUGGCGCGGUGGCUCAUGCUUGUAAUCCCAGCACUUUGGGAGGCUGAGGCGGGCAGAUCAACUGAGAUCGGGGGUUCGAGACCAGCCUGAUCAACAUGGAGAAACCUGGUCUCUACUAAAAAUACAUAAUUAGCUGGGCGUAGUGGCGCAUACCUGUAAUCCCAGCUACUUGGGUGGCCAAGGCUUGAACCCAGGAGGCGGAGGUUGCGGUGAGCCGAGAUGGCGCCAUUGACUCCAGCCUGGGCAACAAGAGCGUAACUCCAUCUCAAAAAAAUAAUAAUAAUAAAAAUAAAAUGCAGACUGUCAGGUCCUCUCUAGACCCACUGAACUAUCCCGCCCACCCUGGGACGGUCCCCAGUGCCAGUGUUUUACCCAUGUUCCCUCUGUAAGUCUUAUGCACACCGCAAUUUGAGAGCCCCACUGGUAUAAAGUGAGUGAAACCCAGGCAGAGACAGGCAAAAUGGUGAGGCCCGCAUCCUAUUGGUGAGUCACACAGGGAACGCUGAAAUUCAUGGCCUUCUCCAGGCUACUGGGAACCCAUGGGCGGUGAUGGAGGGAGUGGUGCCACCUUCACUUGCUGCUGAGGCUCUUCCCCCUCUCCCCAGCAUACUCCUUACCUGGCUGUCUCUCCUCAUGUAUAAGGAACCUAUAGUGGUGUAGAAUCUACUCUUCUUCCCCCUGUGGCUUCCAGGCCCCCCUGUAUAGCUGCUAUCCAGCCCGAUUUCUCACCACUGGCCCAGGGCUUCCUCCUGCCCCGUGGCUUCACGUCUCUGAACACAUCAAUCUCUGAUGUUCUCUCUCCUUCCAUUGAAUUCCACCAGACACAUUCAGGGUUUACUUCGUAAUGUCUUCAUAUGAGUAUCAAUCAACACCUUCCCCAACUCAAUUGUACUAGGUUGUAGAGCACAAGGAUGGUCUCGUGCUGCUCUGUGGCACCUGUGCCUACACUCCUCUGAGCUUUGAGGAGGCUGCUCUCUUUGCUGACCCCAUGAUCUUUUCUGCCCUUCUGUUAAGGGCAUUGGCCACAGCAACGGGGCAAAUGCCCCAAGCUGGCUGUAAGUGACCCAUCCCUUUGGCUCCCAUGAUUAGACCAAGGAGAGGCAUGGGGUCCAGCUGAGCCAUUCAGAACCAUUCCUUAGCAUUUUCCACUCAAAGGUUAGAGAUGAGAUUUUCUCUUCCCAAGGCUACCUCUGGCCAUGGUUCCAGCUUCAUGGGGGCAAUGGGAUUAGGAAAAUGAGGUCAACCUGCAAAGGAAAGCAGAUGCAAGAGAUGGAGACAGAAUGGGGGUGUCCUGGGGAUCUUGGAGCCUGAAUUCAUUGGCACAAAAGGCAGCAGCAUCCUCACUGUAUCUGCAGUCCAUUUGGACUCAAUAAAAACUUUGAAAGUCACAUGUGUUAUGGAAUUCCUUCUCAGUGACACAUUCAUCUGUGCUCAGUUGUCCCAGCAAGGGUCAGCCCCUCAUACCCCUGCAGCAUCCGCUGCUAUGAAGCAGAGCUGUAAACGCCCUCCCUGUGUAUAGGAAAAGCUACAUGGAGCAAAUCCUCCUGCCUGAAGAAGUGCAUCUCAGCAUCACUUCAGCUGUCGGGGCAUUUGUGGGGAGAACCAGACCACCUCUGCGGAAGGCAGCAGACCCUCUUCCAGCCAUGGAUGGAGUUGAAUUCUCUAUAAACGGUUCACCAGCAAACCACCAAUACAUUCCAUUGUUUGCCUAGAGAGAAAUUUAAAAAUAAAUAAAUGUUCACUUAUAA